CAGGCGAGGGGCUGGGUGGCGGUUGAGACAGCGGCGGUACUGGGAGGCGUAGGUGAGGGUCGCGAGGCUGCCCGAGCUUCUGAGCGAGCGCGGUGCUUUUGGGAACGCGGGACGGGCGAUCUGCGGCGCCAGGAGCUGGGCCGAGGCGCGGCGGCGCGGCUGCCGGCUGCCCUGUGAAUGGGAAGUUACGCGAAGUCCACCCAGCGUUUCUGAGGCAAUCUGAAGGCAAAUCCUGUUUAGACCCAGGCGAAGGUUCCCGGUGACCCGGGCUCUCACCAGCCAAUUGUCCCUUGCCGUCCUCCUGAGGGUGCCUGGAGCUUAAGCACUGUGUGCUCUUGGCCUCCACACUGGGGAUGCCGCUGACUCCCACUGUCCAGGGCUUCCAGUGGAUUCUCCGAGGCCCUGAUGUAGAAACUUCCCCAUUGGGUGCACCAAGAGCAGCCUCACAUGGUGUGGGCUGACAUCAAGAGCUGCCAGAUCCAACAGGAAGAUGGCCAAUCUUUCCUAAGCUGCUCACCUUACAAGAAAACGAAUCGUACUGCUAAGAAUUCAAACUUCAGCAGUCAUGGGGAGCCUUGGAAGGAGCCCGAAUCACUGAUGGAAUUGGACAGUGCAUGGAGAUGGUUCAGCAGGACAAGGUGCUGAAAACUCAUCCCCGUGUGACCUCAAGUAAGCCAUGUAACUCUGUGAACCUGCAGUUUUAUCAUUUUUAAAAUAAAGAAACAUGACAGAUUUUCAUUAUGACACAGAAUGUCAGGUCUCCCAGAUGCCAGAAAAUACAUUUACUUAAAGCCGUUGAUACGUCUUAAAGCGGUUUCCUUACAGUGUCAUUGGAGGACAGUGUGGAGUGCAGAGAGACAUGCUUUGAAAUGGGAUUGAUCCAGUCCUCCUUCCUUCACUACCACAUGAAUGCUGGGCAGCCCAGGGUCAACCCACCGCACCCUCAACUCAGUGGAUACAGACAAAACUGCAGAAGACCCAGAGGAAAUCAGGGCAGGCUAAAAGUUUGAUAUCUUACACCUGUGGAAAAGCCUUAAGCUCUGUUUUAACUGAGAGCAGGUGGGGUGACUUCAUGACUACCAUUAAGAAAAUACAACCUGUUGGGAAACUGUUUCUGCCUUGAUGAUGUUGUACAGACAAGAGAUAAACAGUGAGGAAUAUGCUUAGAUGUAUUGGGAAAGACACGGGUCUGUGGCAUCAUCACAAGGGUACACGAAUACUGAGAGUGAAUGCUGAAGGAAUGAUCCCCAUUGGUGGUGACCCUCAGACGGUUACCUGGCACGCUGGCCACAGUCUACCUCACUCUUAUCAGAGUCUGAGCUACUGGCAGUGCUUUCAGCUCUGAGUUCAGGCACCUCGAACCUUGUUUUUGUGGUGAAGGAUCCUAAAGUGCUGUGGGGAGUGAUCACAUUUUUCACAACAUCCCUGGCUCCACCUCUUCUGCCACAAACGUCAGCAUGGUGGUAUCAGCCGGCCCUUGGUCCAGCGAGAAGGCAGAGACGAACAUUCUAGAAAUGAAUGAGAAAUUGCGCCCCCAGCUGGCAGAGAAGAAACAGCAGUUCAGAAACCUCAAAGAGAAAUGUUUUGUAACUCAACUGGCCGGCUUCCUGGCCAACCGACAGAAGAAAUACAAGUAUGAAGAGUGUAAAGACGUCAUAAAAUUUAUGCUGAGGAAUGAGCGACAGUUCAAGGAGGAGAAGCUUGCAGAGCAGCUCAAGCAAGCUGAGGAGCUCAGGCAAUAUAAAGUCCUGGUUCACUCUCAGGAACGAGAGCUGACCCAGUUAAGGGAGAAGUUACGGGAAGGGAGAGAUGCCUCCCGCUCAUUGAAUCAGCAUCUCCAGGCCCUCCUCACUCUGGAUGAGCCAGACAAGUCCCAGGGGCAGGACCUGCAAGAACAGCUGGCUGAGGGGUGUAGACUGGCACAGCAACUUUUCCAAAAGCUCAGCCCAGAAAAUGACGAAGAUGAGGAUGAAGAUGUUCAAGUUGAGGAGGCUGAGAAAGUACUGGAAUCAUCUGCCCCCAGGGAGGUGCAGAAGGCUGAAGAAAGCAAAGUCCCUGAGGACUCACUGGAGGAAUGUGCCAUCACUUGUUCAAAUAGCCACGGCCCUUGUGACUCCAACCAGCCUCACAAGAACAUCAACAUCACAUUUGAGGAAGACAAAGUCAACUCAGCUCUGGUUGUAGACAGAGAAUCCUCUCAUGAUGAAUGUCAGGAUGCUGUAAACAUUCUCCCAGUCCCUGGCCCCACCUCUUCUGCCACAAACGUCAGCAUGGUGGUAUCAGCCGGCCCUUUGUCCAGCGAGAAGGCAGAGAUGAACAUUCUAGAAAUCAACGAGAAAUUGCAUCCCCAGCUGGCAGAGAAGAAACAGCAGUUCAGAAACCUCAAAGAGAAAUGUUUUGUAACUCAACUGGCCGGCUUCCUGGCCAACCAGCAGAACAAAUACAAAUAUGAAGAGUGCAAAGACCUCAUAAAAUCUAUGCUGAGGAAUGAGCGACAGUUCAAGGAGGAGAAGCUUGCAGAGCAGCUCAAGCAAGCUGAGGAGCUCAGGCAAUAUAAAGUCCUGGUUCACUCUCAGGAACGAGAGCUGACCCAGUUAAGGGAGAAGUUACGGGAAGGGAGAGAUGCCUCCCGCUCAUUGAAUCAGCAUCUCCAGGCCCUCCUCACUCCGGAUAAGCCAGACAAGUCCCAGGGGCAGGACCUGCAAGAACAGCUGGCUGAGGGGUGUAGACUGGCACAGCACCUUGUCCAAAAGCUCAGCCCAGAAAAUGACGAAGAUGAGGAUGAAGAUGUUCAAGUUGAGGAGGCUGAGAAAGUACUGGAAUCAUCUGCCCCCAGGGAGGUGCAGAAGGCUGAAGAAAGCAAAGUCCCUGAGGACUCACUGGAGGAAUGUGCCAUCACUUGUUCAAAUAGCCACGGCCCUUGUGACUCCAACCAGCCUCACAAGAACAUCAACAUCACAUUUGAGGAAGACAAAGUCAACUCAGCUCUGGUUGUAGACAGAGAAUCCUCUCAUGAUGAAUGUCAGGAUGCUGUAAACAUUCUCCCAGUCCCUGGCCCCACCUCUUCUGCCACAAACGUCAGCAUGGUGGUAUCAGCCGGCCCUUUGUCCAGCGAGAAGGCAGAGAUGAACAUUCUAGAAAUGAAUGAGAAAUUGCGCCCCCAGCUGGCAGAGAAGAAACAGCAGUUCAGAAACCUCAAAGAGAAAUGUUUUGUAACUCAACUGGCCGGCUUCCUGGCCAACCAGCAGAACAAAUACAAAUAUGAAGAGUGCAAAGACCUCAUAAAAUCUAUGCUGAGGAAUGAGCGACAGUUCAAGGAGGAGAAGCUUGCAGAGCAGCUCAAGCAAGCUGAGGAGCUCAGGCAAUAUAAAGUCCUGGUUCACUCUCAGGAACGAGAGCUGACCCAGUUAAGGGAGAAGUUACGGGAAGGGAGAGAUGCCUCCCGCUCAUUGAAUCAGCAUCUCCAGGCCCUCCUCACUCCGGAUGAGCCAGACAAGUCCCAGGGGCAGGACCUCCAAGAACAGCUGGCUGAGGGGUGUAGACUGGCACAGCACCUUGUCCAAAAGCUCAGCCCAGAAAAUGACAACGAUGACGAUGAAGAUGUUCAAGUUGAGGUGGCUGAGAAAGUGCAGAAAUCGUCUGCCCCCAGGGACAUGCAGAAGGCUGAAGAAAAGGAAGUCCCUGAGGACUCACUGGAGGAAUGUGCCAUCACUUGUUCAAAUAGCCAUGGCCCUUAUGACUCCAACCAGCCACAUAGGAAAACCAAAAUCACAUUUGAGGAAGACAAAGUCGACUCAACUCUCAUUGGCUCAUCCUCUCAUGUUGAAUGGGAGGAUGCUGUACACAUUAUCCCAGAAAAUGAAAGUGAUGAUGAGGAAGAGGAAGAAAAAGGGCCAGUGUCUCCCAGGAAUCUGCAGGAGUCUGAAGAGGAGGAAGUCCCCCAGGAGUCCUGGGAUGAAGGUUAUUCGACUCUCUCAAUUCCUCCUGAAAUGUUGGCCUCGUACCAGUCUUACAGCGGCACAUUUCACUCAUUAGAGGAACAGCAAGUCUGCAUGGCUGUUGACAUAGGCGGACAUCGGUGGGAUCAAGUGAAAAAGGAGGACCAAGAGGCAACAGGUCCCAGGCUCAGCAGGGAGCUGCUGGAUGAGAAAGGGCCUGAAGUCUUGCAGGACUCACUGGAUAGAUGUUAUUCAACUCCUUCAGGUUAUCUUGAACUGACUGACUCAUGCCAGCCCUACAGAAGUGCCUUUUACAUAUUGGAGCAACAGCGUGUUGGCUGGGCUCUUGACAUGGAUGAAAUUGAAAAGUACCAAGAAGUGGAAGAAGACCAAGACCCAUCAUGCCCCAGGCUCAGCAGGGAGCUGCUGGAUGAGAAAGAGCCUGAAGUCUUGCAGGACUCACUGGAUAGAUGUUAUUCGACUCCUUCAGGUUAUCUUGAACUGCCUGACUUAGGCCAGCCCUACAGAAGUGCUGUUCACUCAUUGGAGGAACAGUACCUUGGCUUGGCUCUUGACGUGGACAGAAUUAAAAAGGACCAGGAAGAGGAAGAAGACCAAGGCCCACCAUGCCCCAGGCUCAGCAGGGAGCUGCUGGAGGCAGUAGAGCCUGAAGUCUUGCAGGACUCACUGGAUAGAUGUUAUUCAACUCCUUCCAGUUGUCUUGAACAGCCUGACUCCUGCCUGCCCUAUGGAAGUUCCUUUUAUGCAUUGGAGGAAAAACAUGUUGGCUUUUCUCUUGACGUGGGAGAAAUUGAAAAGAAGGGGAAGGGGAAGAAAAGAAGGGGAAGAAGAUCAACGAAGAAAAGAAGGAGAAGGGGAAGAAAAGAAGGGGAAGAAGAUCAAAACCCACCAUGCCCCAGGCUCAGCAGGGAGCUGCUGGAUGAGAAAGGGCCUGAAGUCUUGCAGGACUCACUGGAUAGAUGUUAUUCAACUCCUUCAGGUUAUCUUGAACUGACUGACUCAUGCCAGCCCUACAGAAGUGCCUUUUACAUAUUGGAGCAACAGCGUGUUGGCUGGGCUCUUGACAUGGAUGAAAUUGAAAAGUACCAAGAAGUGGAAGAAGACCAAGACCCAUCAUGCCCCAGGCUCAGCAGGGAGCUGCUGGAUGAGAAAGAGCCUGAAGUCUUGCAGGACUCACUGGAUAGAUGUUAUUCGACUCCUUCAGGUUAUCUUGAACUGCCUGACUUAGGCCAGCCCUACAGAAGUGCUGUUCACUCAUUGGAGGAACAGUACCUUGGCUUGGCUCUUGACGUGGACAGAAUUAAAAAGGACCAGGAAGAGGAAGAAGACCAAGGCCCACCAUGCCCCAGGCUCAGCAGGGAGCUGCUGGAGGCAGUAGAGCCUGAAGUCUUGCAGGACUCACUGGAUAGAUGUUAUUCAACUCCUUCCAGUUGUCUUGAACAGCCUGACUCCUGCCUGCCCUAUGGAAGUUCCUUUUAUGCAUUGGAGGAAAAACAUGUUGGCUUUUCUCUUGACGUGGGAGAAAUUGAAAAGAAGGGGAAGGGGAAGAAAAGAAGGGGAAGAAGAUCAACGAAGAAAAGAAGGAGAAGGGGAAGAAAAGAAGGGGAAGAAGAUCAAAACCCACCAUGCCCCAGGCUCAGCAGGGAGCUGCUGGAUGAGAAAGGGCCUGAAGUCUUGCAGGACUCACUGGAUAGAUGUUAUUCAACUCCUUCAGGUUAUCUUGAACUGACUGACUCAUGCCAGCCCUACAGAAGUGCCUUUUACAUAUUGGAGCAACAGCGUGUUGGCUGGGCUCUUGACAUGGAUGAAAUUGAAAAGUACCAAGAAGUGGAAGAAGACCAAGACCCAUCAUGCCCCAGGCUCAGCAGGGAGCUGCUGGAUGAGAAAGAGCCUGAAGUCUUGCAGGACUCACUGGAUAGAUGUUAUUCGACUCCUUCAGGUUAUCUUGAACUGCCUGACUUAGGCCAGCCCUACAGAAGUGCUGUUCACUCAUUGGAGGAACAGUACCUUGGCUUGGCUCUUGACGUGGACAGAAUUAAAAAGGACCAGGAAGAGGAAGAAGACCAAGGCCCACCAUGCCCCAGGCUCAGCAGGGAGCUGCUGGAGGCAGUAGAGCCUGAAGUCUUGCAGGACUCACUGGAUAGAUGUUAUUCAACUCCUUCCAGUUGUCUUGAACAGCCUGACUCCUGCCUGCCCUAUGGAAGUUCCUUUUAUGCAUUGGAGGAAAAACAUGUUGGCUUUUCUCUUGACGUGGGAGAAAUUGAAAAGAAGGGGAAGGGGAAGAAAAGAAGGGGAAGAAGAUCAACGAAGAAAAGAAGGAGAAGGGGAAGAAAAGAAGGGGAAGAAGAUCAAAACCCACCAUGCCCCAGGCUCAGCGGUGUGCUGAUGGAAGUGGAAGAGCCUGAAAUCUUGCAGGACUCACUGGAUAGAUGUUAUUCGACUCCGUCAAUGUUCUUUGAACUACCUGACUCAUUCCAGCACUACAGAAGUGUGUUUUACUCAUUUGAGGAACAGCACAUCAGCUUCGCCCUUGACGUGGACAAUAGGUUUCUUACUUUGAUGGGAACAAGUCUCCACCUGGUCUUCCAGAUGGGAGUCAUAUUCCCACAGUAAGCAGCCCUUACUAAGCCGAGAGAUGUCAUUCCUGCAGGCAGGACCUAUAGGCACGUGAAGAUUUGAAUGAAACUAUAGUUCCAUUUGGAAGCCCAGACAUAGGAUGGGUCAGUGGGCAUGGCUCUAUUCCUAUUCUCAGACCAUGCCAGUGGCAACCUGUGCUCAGUCUGAAGACAAUGGACCCAAGUUAGGUGUGACACGUUCACAUAACUGUGCAGCACAUGCCGGGAGUGAUCAGUCAGACAUUUUAAUUUGAACCACGUAUCUCUGGGUAGCUACAAAGUUCCUCAGGGAUUUCAUUUUGCAGGCAUGUCUCUGAGCUUCUAUACCUGCUCAAGGUCAGUGUCAUCUUUGUGUUUAGCUCAUCCAAAGGUGUUACCCUGGUUUCAAUGAACCUAACCUCAUUCUUUGUAUCUUCAGUGUUGAAUUGUUUUAGCUGAUCCAUCUUUAACACAGGAGGGAUCCUUGGCUGAGGAUUGUAUUUCAGAACCACCAACUGCUCUUGACAAUUGUUAACCCGCUAGGCUCCUUUGGUUAGAGAAGCCACAGUCCUUCAGCCUCCAAUUGGUGUCAGUACUUAGGAAGACCACAGCUAGAUGGACAAACAGCAUUGGGAGGCCUUAGCCCUGCUCCUCUCGAUUCCAUCCUGUAGAGAACAGGAGUCAGGAGCCGCUGGCAGGAGACAGCAUGUCACCCAGGACUCUGCCGGUGCAGAAUAUGAACAACGCCAUGUUCUUGCAGAAAACGCUUAGCCUGAGUUUCAUAGGAGGUAAUCACCAGACAACUGCAGAAUGUAGAACACUGAGCAGGACAACUGACCUGUCUCCUUCACAUAGUCCAUAUCACCACAAAUCACACAACAAAAAGGAGAAGAGAUAUUUUGGGUUCAAAAAAAGUAAAAAGAUAAUAUAGCUGCAUUUCUUUAGUUAUUUUGAACCCCAAAUAUUUCCUCAUCUUUUUGUUGUUGUCAUUGAUGGUGGUGACAUGGACUUGUUUAUAGAGGACAGGUCAGCUGUCUGGCUCAAUGAUCUACAUUCUGAAGUUGUCUGAAAAUGUCUUCAUGAUUAAAUUCAGCCUAAACGUUUUGCCGGGAACACUGCAGAGACAAUGCUGUGAGUUUCCAACCUUAGCCCAUCUGCGGGCAGAGAAGGUCUAGUUUGUCCAUCAGCAUUAUCAUGAUAUCAGGACUGGUUACUUGGUUAAGGAGGGGUCUAGGAGAUCUGUCCCUUUUAGAGACACCUUACUUAUAAUGAAGUAUUUGGGAGGGUGGUUUUCAAAAUUAGAAAUGUCCUGUAUUCCGAUGAUCAUCCUGUAAACAUUUUAUCAUUUAUUAAUCAUCCCUGCCUGUGUCUAUUAUUAUAUUCAUAUCUCUACGCUGGAAACUUUCUGCCUCAAUGUUUACUGUGCCUUUGUUUUUGCUAGUGUGUGUUGUUGAAAAAAAAAACAUUCUCUGCCUGAGUUUUAAUUUUUGUCCAAAGUUAUUUUAAUCUAUACAAUUAAAAGCUUUUGCCUAUCA